ACUAGCCCCAAGAACAAAAGAGGCACAGGUGGGAACAACUCUCCCAAAACCAGGACUGGGAGCAUGGCCAAACUUCAUAGUGAGCUUACUUGCCUCUGACACACAAGGCAGCAGUGAGCUGGCUACAGCUCCAGCCAUUAAUAGCUCAGCCAGGACAGGGAAUAAGACUUCCCUGGUUCUUCUUUUGGCUUUGCUGAAACAGAAAUAGAGCUGUUAUAUUACAUGCAUGAAGGACAUGCAUGAAGCAUGGAUGUCAGCCAGAGUUGAACAAGGCAGAUGUUCCUGUUGGACACAGUAAGAACGAGUCUGAAAAACAAAUUGAGAAUCUGACUUCCAAUCAAUAAUCUUUCUCCAUGACCACAGUUGGGGACUUCUGCCCACACUUAUAGCUACAGGAAACUGGACAAGAAUAAGUGAGUUUAUCCUCAUGAGCUUCUCUUCCCUGCCUACUGAAAUACAGUCAUUACUCUUUCUGACAUUUCUAACCAUCUACCUGGUCACCCUGAUGGGAAACUGCCUCAUCAUUCUGGUUACCCUAGCUGACCCCAUGCUACACAGCCCCAUGUACUUCUUCCUCAGAAACUUAUCUUUCCUGGAGAUUGGCUUCAACCUAGUCAUUGUGCCCAAAAUGCUGGGGACCCUGCUUGCCCAGGACACAACCAUCUCCUUCCUUGGCUGUGCCACUCAGAUGUAUUUCUUCUUCUUCUUUGGAGUGGCUGAAUGCUUCCUCCUGGCUACCAUGGCAUAUGACCGCUAUGUGGCCAUCUGCAGUCCCUUGCACUACCCAGUCAUCAUGAACCAAAGGACUCGUGCCAAACUGGCUGCUGCCUCCUGGUUCCCAGGCUUUCCUGUAGCUACUGUGCAGACCACAUGGCUCUUCAGUUUUCCAUUCUGUGGCACCAACAAGGUGAACCACUUCUUCUGUGACAGCCCACCUGUGCUGAGGCUGGUCUGUGCAGACACAGCACUCUUUGAGAUCUACGCCAUCGUCGGAACCAUUCUGGUGGUCAUGAUCCCCUGCUUGCUGAUCUUGUGUUCCUAUACUCACAUUGCUGCUGCCAUCCUCAAGAUCCCAUCAGCUAAAGGGAAGAAUAAAGCCUUUUCUACAUGUUCCUCACACCUCCUUGUUGUCUCUCUUUUCUAUAUAUCAUUAAGCCUCACCUACUUCCGGCCUAAAUCAAAUAAUUCACCUGAGGGCAAGAAGCUGCUAUCAUUGUCCUACACUGUUAUGACUCCCAUGUUGAACCCCAUUAUCUACAGCCUGAGAAAUAACGAGGUGAAGAAUGCCCUCAGCAGGACGGUCUCUAAGGCCCUAGCCCUCAGAAACUGUAUCCCAUAGACCUUAGGAAGUAAGGCUACAUUUUACUGGAUGAGAAACAAUCAGUCCCAGAUUUGAGAUUCCUCUCUGCAUCUUUCCACAUCUCCAAUAAGAUGAAGUCCUGUUGCUGAAAUGGCUUUUGGAAAGCUGAGUGGAGAGAAAGGAGCAGAGAAGUAGUUUCGACCUAGCACCACCAACUAUGAAAACUCCUCUGCCUGCCCAUUGUAGACUUACAUUGUUUUCCUUGUUUCAACUGGUAUGACAGCACUUCUGUGGCCAACUAUUUCCAGGUGUUAUAUUUCUUUUUUUUUUUUUUUUUGAGACGGAGUCUCGCUCUGUCCCCCAGGCUGGAGUGCAGUGGCGCAUCUCUGCUCACUGCAAGCUCCGCCUCCUGGGUUCACGCUGUUCUCCUGCCUCAGCCUCCCAAGUAGCUGGGACUACAGGUGCCCGCCACCAUGCCCGGCUAAUUUUUUGUAUUUUUUUAGUAGAGACAGGGUUUCACCGUGUUAGCCAGGAUGGUCUCGAUCUCCUGACCUCGUGAUCCACCCGCCUCGGCCUCCCAAAGUGCUGGGAUUACAGGCGUGAGCCACCGCGCCUGGCCGGUGUUUAUAUUUCUGUGUGACGUGCAUUGUGCACAAUAUGAAACUGCUAGUCAUUAUAACAUGGGGGCACACAUAGUAACAGAGGGUAAAACCCAAUAAAAAUCAUCUUGUCACUUUUCCUCUUCUGGGCAGAUCUGACUCUACAUUCAUGACAGAAAAUCUCAUGAUCUUUCCCAACACAUAACUCUCCUCACCAUCUUACUUCAUUCUCAUGCCCUUAAGCAGUGUUAGUUCUUUUAAGCUUACUGGUAUGCAGUAUGCAUGUAUGAGAGUAGAUCAAAAGUUCACAUGCAUAUGCCUUUAUAACCCCAAUAAUUAUUUCCUUCACACUAGAUUCUUCCCAAGAAAAACAACCUGAGCUUCCCUAAGAUCUCUAUUCCAUAUUCAGGUUCUUAUGUUUUGUUGAAGUAAUAUCGUAAAUUUCAGUCAUAGCUUUGCUUUGAUGAGAACAAAGCUCCAGAAUAAGUCUUCUUUAACCACAAGAUUUCUCCUUCUUAUAAUCUGGUAGUACUCUAUUUGUAGAUGUGCCCUAAUUUAUUUAGCCAGUCUUUUACUACUACAAAUCAUGCUGUAAAUAAUGGACUUAUCCAUAUAUCUGUUUUUAUAUUUUUGCUAGUGUACCUGACAAAUAGAAAUCUAGAAAUUGAGUUUCUUGGGCAAAAGUUAAAUACAUACAUAAUGUUGCUAUAUAUAUUGAUUGUCUAUCUAGCUCCCCUCUGAACUUAUUGCACCAUUUUAUGCUCCCACCAGCAAUUUAUGAGGUGUUUGUUUCCCCACAACUCAACAAUAACAUUUCUCAUGAAAUAUUUAGAAUUUCGAUUAUUUAAUAUUUUAUAAAAACUCAAUGAAAUUUUAAUUUGAAUGAAAUAAAUUUUGAAGAAUAAGAAAGAAACAGAUGAUCAAAUCAGAGGAAAGGUGUGCAUUUCAUUGAAACUUGAGUUAUAGAUUAGACGAUUAGCAAUUGGUGAUGUCUUGGUGUUUUAUUUUCUCUUCUUGAAAGGUUGUUUUUCACUUUUAUUUUAGCCAAAUCUAUCCCAUCUCUCAAGACCCCACUGUGAUUCCUCAAGAAGCAGAAAUCACUCUUUCUGUAUGCACCCAUUUCAAGUUUAUUAAUAAAUACAUUAAAUUUUGUAUAUACUACAUGUAGAAACUGUACAUGUACUUAUUUUUACAUGUUUGUCUUCCUCCAACUUUUCUGUAACUCUUCAAAAAUAAGAAUUGUUCAAGUGUUUCUGGUGUUUUGUUUUGUGUUUGAGACAGGGUCUCUCUCUCUGUCACCCAGGCUGGACUGCGGUAGCAGAAUUAUGGCUCACUGUAGCCUCAAACACCUGGGCUCAGGCCAUCUUCCUGCCUCAGUCUCCCUAGUGGCUGGGACUAUAGGCGUACAUCACCAUGCCUGGCCAUUUAAAAAUUUUUUUUUAGUAGAGACGAGGUCUUGCUAUGCUACCCAGUCUGGUAUCGAACUUCUGAGUUCAAGCAAUCCUUCUGCCUGAACCUCUCAAAGUGCUGGGAUUAUAAGUGUGAGCCAUUGCAUGCAACACAAGUGUUUCUCUUUUCUUUUCUUUCUUUCUUUUUUUUUUUUUUUUUGAGACAAAGGUCUGCUCUAUUACUCAGGCUGCUGGGGUGCAAUGGCACAAUCUUGGCUCACUGCAACUUCUGCCUUCUGGGUUCAAUCAAUUCUCAUGCCUCAGCCUCUUGAGUAGCUGGGAUUACAGGCGUGCCAAGCCAUGCCCAACUAAUUUUUUUUUUGUAUUUUUUAGUAGAGAUGCAGUUUUACCAUGUUGGAGCUCCUGGCCUCAAGUGAUCUGCCUGCCUCAGCCUCCCAAGGGCUGGGAUUACAGACGUGGGCCACCAUGCCAGGCCAAGUAUUUCCCUUUUAAUAUGACGUAGGCAUUCCUGAAAAGCUUAUGUAAUGCAAACCUUUACAUUAAAAAUAUUAUGGGGAAGUAGGGCUAGGGUUAGGGCUAGACUCAAAAUACAUGCAACUUUAAAGACAAGGCAUUAGUAGAAACAACAUUUGGUUCCCAGAGAGACAAUGUAGACUGCCCAGGCAGGCAGCUCAUUGAGGCUGGAGGUUGCCACAGUAGAUAUUUAAAAUAUACAACAACAGUAGAAUGAAAAUACCAACAAUGCUUGGAUUAGAACAAUGAUGCUUGAUGCUGAGACAAUUUGUACUGGGGUAGGGGGUAGUCCUUAGUAUGGGUAAAGAAUUUGAAGUAAAGCAAACAAGAAUAACCCAAAACCUAAAGAAAAAGUUGUACAUAGUUUCAGGGAAAGGAUUCCAACAGAAGAGUGCCACAUGCACAAACACAGGAGUGCUGAGAGACUAUGAUGUGUGUAAGGAACACAAAGCAUUUUUGUGUCACUGAAAAAUCAGCUACACUGGGGAUUUGAAACUGGAAAAAUAAGCAGAGAUCACAGGAAAAGACCUUGUUAAAGGAUUUACUUUAUCCCAGGGGCCAUACGGAGUAAUUGAAAGACAUUAAGCAGGUAAGUGACUUAACCAGAGUUGCUGGUUAAGACAGCAACUGGUAAGACAGUUGCUGAUAAGACAGAUCACAUACAAACCAAGGAUGGUUUGAAGAGAAUGAACCAGAAGCAGGUUCCUACCAUACUCUAGGCCAGAGAAAAUAAAUCCAGAACCUAAAGGCAGUGGUGGUAGAGCUGGAGAAGGUGACACUGAAUUAGUGUUUAGGAGUAAAAAUAAUCAAAUUUGGGGCACAAAUUAAAGGAUUAUAUCCCAGUUCCUGGCUUGUACUUUGGGGUGGUGCCAUUUACUGAAAUGGGGUAUCUACAAAGAGGAGGUUUGAGGUGGAGGAAGCAGACAAGCACAUUUAUAUCUCUUAUCAUUGUUUCAGUCCGUGUGAAUUGUAUGAUGCUAUAUUAUAUUCUUUUGUGCCUUUGUCUAAAUUCCUUAUGAAUGGGGCUCACUGUACCUACUUUGUGUCUGUGUAGAUGUUUCCCUGAUUAUUUACCACAUUUUCUUCAUUAUCUAUUAAAUUAUUCAAUAACAAUUUACUGGGCAUCUACCUUUCUAGGCAUUGGGGUAAAAAAAUGAAUAACACAAUUUCUAUUUCAAGGAGCAUGUCAUCUACUGUAUGAGACAAAUACAUACAAUAAUGAUUAUUCUAAAAUAAGAACUAUGAAAGUGGUAUUCCAGUUCUCCAAUGUUACUAAUAUAUUGAAAUUUUCUGCCCAUCUUUAGAAAUUGUGUUGCUUUGUUCUUACUACCACCCUGUACUGGAUACUGGCUUGUCCUCACCUGUGGGCUCAGAUUUAUUCCCAUUCUGAAAAAAUGAGUGCAAGUGUCACUUGUCGGCCAAAUCCCUGACUUGGACUCAGCCACCCAGGAUUCCAACACUUGCUGAAAAAACUACUCAACUUAUCUGUGUCUCAGAUUCCUUGACUGUAAAAUGGGUAUAAUACUAUCUGUAUCUUCAGGUGUUGUGAGAAUCAAAUAAGAUAAUACA